GCUUUAGAAAGACUUGGACCCAGCUUCUCUGAGCGUUAGCAGGGUGGACUGGAUGGGCCAUAUGCCAGAUCCUUUGAUUUCUAUUUGCCACCACACGAACUGACACUGCUGCCCAGAAGCAUUCCCCUGCACAUCCACAUCACAGCCCUCCUGCUGGCAGCUUGGAAUUUAGACCUUUUACUCUCAAUGCUCCAGGAAACCAGAUGUACUUCUUUCUUUCUUGUCCAUUGGUGAUAUCCUUGACAAUGUAGUUUAGCUUUACAGGUACGUUGUGUCAAGUGGAGAAGAUCAGUUCUGGUUAGCAGCUUUAUUGCCACAGAAAGGACACUGGCAGAUACUUCUCAUAGCUCUAGUCAUGCUGAAUUCCCGGAAAGGGGUGUCAGAAUGAAUUGCUCUAAGCUCUUCUCCCUGGUAGAAGAACCUGUGACUUCUCUUGGAGAUCUCUUCAAUUUUCGCCCAAGGAGCUUGUCAUGGACCAUGGGCAUGGAGGGUCUUCUCCAGAACUCCACUAACUUCGUCCUCACAGGCCUCAUCACCCAUCCUGCCUUCCCCGGGCUUCUCUUUGCAAUAGUCUUCUCCAUCUUUGUGGUGGCUAUAACAGCCAACUUGGUCAUGAUUCUGCUCAUCCACAUGGACUCCCGCCUCCACACACCCAUGUACUUCUUGCUCAGCCAGCUCUCCAUCAUGGAUACCAUCUACAUCUGUAUCACUGUCCCCAAGAUGCUCCAGGACCUCCUGUCCAAGGACAAGACCAUUUCCUUCCUGGGCUGUGCAGUUCAGAUCUUCCUCUACCUGACCCUGAUUGGAGGGGAAUUCUUCCUGCUGGGUCUCAUGGCCUAUGACCGCUAUGUGGCUGUGUGCAACCCUCUACGGUACCCUCUCCUCAUGAACCGCAGGGUUUGCUUAUUCAUGGUGGUCGGCUCCUGGGUUGGUGGUUCCUUGGAUGGGUUCAUGCUGACUCCUGUCACUAUGAGUUUCCCCUUCUGUAGAUCCCGAGAGAUCAAUCACUUUUUCUGUGAGAUCCCAGCCGUGCUGAAGUUGUCUUGCACAGACACGUCACUCUAUGAGACCCUGAUGUAUGCCUGCUGCGUGCUGAUGCUGCUUAUCCCUCUAUCUGUCAUCUCUGUCUCCUACACGCACAUCCUCCUGACUGUCCACAGGAUGAACUCUGCUGAGGGCCGGCGCAAAGCCUUUGCUACGUGUUCCUCCCACAUUAUGGUGGUGAGCGUUUUCUACGGGGCAGCCUUCUACACCAACGUGCUGCCCCACUCCUACCACACUCCAGAGAAAGAUAAAGUGGUGUCUGCCUUCUACACCAUCCUCACCCCCAUGCUCAACCCACUCAUCUACAGCUUGAGGAAUAAAGAUGUGGCUGCAGCUCUGAGGAAAGUACUAGGGAGAUGUGGUUCCUCCCAGAGCAUCAGGGUGGCGACUGUGAUCAGGAAGGGCUAGCAGGGACUCCCACAGCAUCAGAGUGGUGACUGUGAUCGGGAAGGAUUAGCGGGGACUCCCAGAGCAUCAGGGGUGGUGACUGAUCAGGAAGGACUAGCAAGGACUAGCGCAAACAUCUGCGGUGCUGCGGCCAAUAACGCAGCUAUUACAGAAAAUAUGGUAUUGGUUCUGAAGAAUGUUCAGUGUCACUUUCAGCAAUUCAAAAUUAACAGGCAAAAUCAUCCUGUUGCAAGGAUUACUUAGGAACAGUAGCGAAGUUGGUGAGCAUCUCCGCAUUAGUCAACUUUGUUCAACUGGAUUCACAAACAUUUCCAGAGGGCAUUCUCAGUCAAGUAGCCCUACAAACCAUUCAUGGCACGCCAAGCAGCUCUUGGAAGUGCCCAUGUUAACAUGUGACCAUGAGUCCUUCCUGUCUGUAUUGCUAACGUGUGAUCAUGAGUCCUGCCUGCCUGUAUUGCUGACGUGUGAUCAUGAGUCCUGCCUGUCUGUAUUGCUAACGUGUGAUGAGUCCUUCUGUGUCUGUAUUGCUAACGUGUGAUCGUGAGUCCUUCCUGUCUAUAUUGCUAAUGUGUGACCAUGAGUCCUGCCUGUCUGUAUUGCUAACGUGUGACCAUGAGUCCUGCCUGUCUGUAUUGCUAACGUGUGAUCAUGGGUCCUGCCUGUCUGUAUUGCUAACGUGUGAUCAUGGGUCCUGCCUGUCUGUAUUGCUAACACGUGAUUGAGUCCUGCCUGUCUCUAUUGUUAACCUGUGAUCAUGAGUCCUGCCUGUCUGUCUGUAUUGCUGACCAACUUUUGAAUGGAAAUUGGAAGGAGCAUUUGCCACCUCCUUGAUGACUUAAUUUCAAACAUUCAAUACAAGUAAAAUAUUUUCUAGUGCUAAAUGUGUAGCAAUUUUAUUAGAAAACAUUUAGGAAGGUGAUACUAUUUUUGGUUCCAUGUUCUUAGUUACAUUUUAUGAAUGUUAUCACUUACCUCUGAAAUUAAAUACUUGCCCUGCCUUUAUUCACAUGGAGUCCAAUAUAUUCCUGGAAAUAUUGAUUCAUUGAUUGAAAAUUGACUCUGCCAUUAAGAUUGUUACAUGGCCAAAAACCUACAAAACUGCCAUUUAUGCUCAAAUUGUUAAUAGAUAAAUGUAGAAUGAAUAAACCAAGACAUUUUAUUAGCUAACUUAGUUCCCGUGGAAUAAGUUGCUCAAUUUUCUUAUUCUCAACAUCUUCAUUGAUAUGCUGAAGACAAGUAUUUUUGUAAUUAGUUGGAGUUAGGUGUGGUGCUUUGAUAGAUGUGUAACUUUGGUGGAAUACUAACUAAGCAAAGACUACACUGACCCCACCAUUCAUGUAACUUUAGUUUCUCCUGUGUGUAAGGUCCUGAAAUAUGAGACAUAAAAAAUAUUGACGGACCUGGUGUUUAUUUUCUUUGUUGAUACGAGGCUUAGAAAACAUUGGACAGAGCGGUUACAUAGUUGACAAAGACUAAGCAAAGGUUACUCAGCCUUAUGUUGUUCUAGUGUCAACACAGAUAGAAGGAAAAAUGUUUCCUCCAUUGUUGCUGACGUAGAUAAAGAAUAUUCCCUUCAAUAUGCUAACCCCUAGGUGGCUUUUCAUUCAGAAGGUUCCUAAUAAUUUGAUCUUUACCCUGAAAUCAAACACAUGGAAAAGAGAUGGAAGAAUGUCCUGGAGGGAUUAAGUGAAGAAACAGACCAGGAUUCAUUUAUGAAAUAUCCUCGGUGUUAUUUCAAUUCAGCUCCAUUCACAUUUUAUUCUUUUGUGUCUCUGCACUAAUGCCCUCCAUAUUCUCCAUUCUCCUGCCUUAGCUAGCACCUUCUCGAUCUUCCCUCUACAAAACUCCUUCAGUUCACAUUGCAUUUGUGCUCUAUCCUGGGAUAUGUGUUUUCUUUCCCAUUUCCUCAGUUGCUAUGUAUUAAAAAUUAGGACUUUUAUUCUUAUGUUUCCA